CCGGAGUCGAGCGGGUGCUGCUAGCGGAGGCGCCAUAUUGGAGGGGACAAAACUCCGGCGACAGCGAGUGACACAAAUAAACCCCUGGACCCCCUUGUUCCCUCAGCUCUAAGGGCCGCGAUGUUGUACCUAGAAGACUAUCUGGAAAUGAUUGAGCAGCUUCCUAUGGAUCUGCGGGACCGCUUCACGGAAAUGCGCGAGAUGGACCUGCAGGUGCAGAAUGCAAUGGAUCAACUAGAACAAAGAGUCAGUGAAUUCUUUAUGAAUGCAAAGAAAAAUAAACCUGAGUGGAGGGAAGAGCAAAUGGCAUCCAUCAAAAAAGACUACUAUAAAGCUUUGGAAGAUGCAGAUGAGAAGGUUCAGUUGGCAAACCAGAUAUAUGACUUGGUAGAUCGACACUUGAGAAAGCUGGAUCAGGAACUGGCUAAGUUUAAAAUGGAGCUGGAAGCUGAUAAUGCUGGAAUUACAGAAAUAUUAGAGAGGCGAUCUUUGGAAUUAGACACUCCUUCACAGCCAGUGAACAAUCACCAUGCUCAUUCACAUACUCCAGUGGAAAAAAGGAAAUAUAAUCCAACUUCUCACCAUACGACAACAGAUCAUAUUCCUGAAAAGAAAUUUAAAUCUGAAGCUCUUCUAUCCACCCUUACGUCAGAUGCCUCUAAGGAAAAUACACUAGGUUGUCGAAAUAAUAAUUCCACAGCCUCUUCUAACAAUGCCUACAAUGUGAAUUCCUCCCAACCUCUGGGAUCCUAUAACAUUGGCUCGUUAUCUUCAGGAACUGGUGCAGGGGCAAUUACCAUGGCAGCUGCUCAAGCAGUUCAGGCUACAGCUCAGAUGAAGGAGGGACGAAGAACAUCAAGUUUAAAAGCCAGUUAUGAAGCAUUUAAGAAUAAUGACUUUCAGUUGGGAAAAGAAUUUUCAAUGGCCAGGGAAACAGUUGGCUAUUCAUCAUCUUCGGCACUUAUGACAACAUUAACACAGAAUGCCAGUUCAUCAGCAGCCGACUCACGGAGUGGUCGAAAGAGCAAAAACAACAACAAGUCUUCAAGCCAGCAGUCAUCAUCUUCCUCCUCCUCUUCUUCCUUAUCAUCGUGUUCUUCAUCAUCAACUGUUGUACAAGAAAUCUCUCAACAAACAACUGUAGUGCCAGAAUCUGAUUCAAAUAGUCAGGUUGAUUGGACUUACGACCCAAAUGAACCUCGAUACUGCAUUUGUAAUCAGGUAUCUUAUGGUGAGAUGGUGGGAUGUGAUAACCAAGAUUGCCCUAUAGAAUGGUUCCAUUAUGGCUGCGUUGGAUUGACAGAGGCACCAAAAGGCAAAUGGUACUGUCCACAGUGCACUGCUGCAAUGAAGAGAAGAGGCAGCAGACACAAAUAAAGGUGGUCCUUUUGUUUGAUGAAGAAAUAAACUUCAGCUGAAGAUUUUAUAUAGGACUUUAAAAAGAAGAGAAGAGAAAGAAGAAACAAUGCAUUUCCAGGCAACCACUUAAAGGAUUUACAUAGACAAUCCUAUAAGAUCUUGAACUUGAAUUUUAUGGGUUGUAUUUUAAUAAUGUAAGUAAAUUAUUUAUGCACUCCUGGUGUGCUAUGAAUAUUAUUCCAGUUAGCCUUGGAUUAUUUCAGUGGCCAACAUAUGCAGACAUUUGUACUCCUCAACCAUUUUCUCAAAGUAAUGGGCAUUCUAUGAUUUAGACUUCAAGGAAUUCCAAUGAUGAAGAUUUUAAGGAAAGUAUUUUAUAUUCAACAGGUAUAUUCUGCUGCAUGUACUGUACUCCAGAGCUGUUAUGUAACACUGUAUAUAAAUGGUUGCAAAAAAAAAAAAAAGUCAGUGCUUCUAAAAAGAAUUUAAGAUAAUGGUUUUUAAAAUGCCUUUAUAAUAAGCUUUGUUUCUUUGUGAAACUAAUUCAGCAGGCUGAAGGAAAUGGUUCAUGUGAUAAUGUGGGCUGGUAUCCUCUAGAGUACCUGGGUACAUAAACAGAAACUCCUGUAGGUAAAAAGUAAUUUGUGCCAUUAGUCUUUCUAUGUUUCUGCAUCCAGAUAGAGUGCAGUUCAUGAGGGAGGGGGCGGGGGACUGAAGGGGAAAGGGCGUUAAAGUGAUACAUUUUUAUACCAAAUGUGUUUAUUUUUUUGUGCAAGUAAUCCUUAAAAUUGCAAUUGUAUUAGGUGUUAAAAUAAAGUUUUUAAAAAAUUACUUGUAUUUAUACUUUACAUACUUAAUAAUGAAAAUUUCUGAAUUCCAAUUAACUUUCAACUUUCAUAAUCUAAAAAGAAUCAGAGACCCAGGACACAGAAUACUGUGUAAUCUGUGAUGUCUUUAAUGAUGUUUAGAGUUUGUGAUAUAAGAAUACAGGAAAGACAUUUUUAAUGUAAAUUUGAAAUGCCAAUGUAUUUUUUUAAGAACAUCAUCUGGCUUUUCCUUCAGUCUAAAAGACAUGAAAGAAGUGUAAGUAUAGCAGUUAAAACGAAAAUAAUGGUUAUGGGUGUUUUGACUGGAGGCAAUGUAGCCAAAUAGAGUAAAGAGACCCCCCUGGUCGGGAGCUCCAAAUUGAGCUAUUUUUGAUUCUACCACUUACUGAUAUGACAGUUAAUUCAAAUUUUGUAUCACUCUGGGCCUUACUACACCAGGGUGAUGCUGACUGCAGAAUAGAUCUUAUUCUAAGGUGCUAUUUAAAUUAUAAAUUUGCAUAGUGGAGGUUUUAUUUAAAGUAUAAUAUUGAGUCUGGUCGAUAGAAAAAUCCUUAACUUUUAAGAUACUUAAUAUAUCAUAUAUAUUUUAUAUUGAAACUUACUGGGUCCAUCAGAUUUCUGCUUUAAUUAAACCACUUAUGAGCUUCUUAGAACUUAUUCAGAUAACAGUGUAAAAUCUAUGCAGUGCUACCCAAAGGGUGUGAGGUAGAUAGGGGAUUUCAAAGAUCUCUUCCACCUUUGAGAUCCCAUGAUUCUGAGCUGCCACAGUCUGAUUAUACAACUCUACCAGCUCCCUAAACAAGUUAGGUUCAUUUGUGAGUACUCAUCAUUUCAUAAUAUCAUGAUUAUCACGAUUUCAUGAUACUCAAUAUUUUGAGAUUUUAUAACCCUUUAAGAAGUGAUAAAUAAUGUAGUAUUCAAUUCGUUUAUCAAAGUAUAUUGCCUGGAAAUGCUCACAUGUAUCAUUUACAUCCUCUAUAUAUUAUGACUAUUCCAAACUCAUUCAUUUUAUAGAAAUGGUCAAAGGAAAAAGCCUUAUGUACAGCCUUAUUUGAAGAGAAAGUUCUUUGUCUGAGUCAGGAACAUCCUGUUAUCCAGCUGCUACAUCCCCUUUCAGUGUGAAUUCCACUCCUUACCAAAUCACUUAGAAAACACUUUGACAAGUUUUAAACUCAAACACUGAAUAUUUUAUGAAGCAUGUGUAAAGAAAGAAACCAAAAUUUGGUGCAGGUAUUUAGUAAUGGGUAGAACCUGUUAAUAUCUGAGUCAUAUAUAAUGGGGCCAAACAUGGAACUACCUCAUCAACCCCCCAAAAAUGUGGCCAACUAUUAAUAUUCUUUGUGACAUUUACACCAAGGGGCAUAGUAAGUAUUUUUGGUAUUAUAAAAUACACAUUCAAAAUCUCUGUUGUACAAAACUCAUGUAACAGUUGGGACAAAAUAUCCAAAUGUGGGUUCACAGUUCACAGGUGGUGAAAAUUGAGGCCUUACUGCUAUGGAGUGUAUAUCAAAAUGUUCAUGGUGACACAUUUGAAGCAAUAAAUGGCUUAAUUAAAUGCCAAAA